AGUUCCGGAAGCGGAUCGUGUUGGGUGCGGGUGACGCCGCCGAGCGUGAGUGUCCCUCAGUAUGGAUUAAACUUGCGAACCGCCGUGCCCCGUUUCCGCAGCCAGUUCCCGGGCUCGCUACAGACCUUUUUUUUUUUCUUUUUUUUUUUUUUUGGUGAGACGGAGAUUUACUCUUGUUGUCCAGGCUGGAGUGCAAUGGCGCGAUUUCGGCUCACCGCAUCCUCCGCCUCCCAGGUUCAAGCGAUUCUCCUGCCUCAGCCUCCCGAGUAGCUGGGAUUACAGGCAUGUGCCACCACGCCCGGCUAAUUUUGUAUUUUUAGUAGAGACGGGGUUUCACCGUGUUGCCCAGGCUGAUCUCGAACUCCUGACCUCAGGAAGAACCCUUGAAGAAGAGGAAGAGGAAAGAAAGACAAGUCAGGCAUGGCUCUCACCCAGGGACAGGUGACAUUCAGGGAUGUGGCUAUAGAAUUCUCUCAGGAGGAGUGGACAUGCCUGGACCCCGCUCAGAGGACUUUGUACAGGGACGUGAUGUUGGAGAAUUAUAGGAACCUGGCCUCCCUGGCAGGAAUCUCUUGUUUUGACCUCAGUAUUAUCUCUAUGUUGGAGCAAGGGAAGGAGCCUUUCACUUUGGAGAGCCAAGUACAAAUAGCAGGAAACCCAGAUGGAUGGGAAUGGAUCAAAGCUGUGAUCACAGCUCUCUCUUCCGAAUUUGUAAUGAAAGAUUUACUACACAAAGGGAAGAGUAAUACAGGAGAAGUAUUCCAAACAGUGAUGUUGGAAAGACAGGAAAGCCAAGACAUUGAAGGAUGUUCCUUCAGGGAAGUCCAGAAAAAUACACAUGGCCUUGAGUAUCAAUGCAGAGAUGCUGAAGGAAAUUACAAAGGAGUGCUUUUGACCCAAGAAGGCAAUCUCACUCAUGGAAGAGAUGAACAUGAUAAAAGAGAUGCAAGAAACAAGCUUAUUAAAAAUCAGCUUGGAUUAAGCCUUCAGUCACAUCUGCCUGAACUGCAGCUUUUUCAAUAUGAAGGGAAAAUUUAUGAAUGUAAUCAGGUUGAGAAGUCUUUCAACAAUAAUUCCUCAGUUUCACCACCUCAACAAAUGCCUUAUAAUGUCAAAACCCACAUUUCUAAGAAAUAUCUCAAAGAUUUUAUCUCUUCUUUAUUACUCACACAGGGGCAAAAAGCAAAUAAUUGGGGAAGCCCUUACAAAUCUAAUGGAUGUGGCAUGGUCUUUCCUCAAAAUUCACACCUUGCAAGUCAUCAGAGAAGUCAUACUAAAGAGAAACCUUACAAAUGUUAUGAGUGUGGCAAAGCCUUUAGAACACGUUCAAACCUAACUACCCAUCAGGUGAUCCAUACUGGCGAAAAACGUUACAAAUGUAAUGAGUGUGGUAAGGUCUUUAGUCGAAAUUCACAACUCUCACAACAUCAGAAAAUUCACACUGGAGAGAAACCUUAUAAAUGUAACGAAUGUGGCAAGGUCUUCACUCAGAAUUCACACCUUGUAAGACAUCGAGGAAUUCAUACUGGAGAGAAACCUUACAAGUGUAAUGAGUGUGGGAAAGCCUUUAGAGCUCGUUCAAGCUUAGCUAUCCAUCAGGCAACCCACAGUGGAGAAAAACCUUACAAAUGUAAUGAAUGUGGCAAGGUCUUCACUCAAAAUUCACACCUUACAAAUCACUGGAGAAUUCACACUGGAGAGAAACCUUACAAGUGUAAUGAGUGCGGCAAAGCCUUUGGUGUUCGUUCAAGCCUAGCUAUUCAUCUGGUAAUUCACACCGGAGAAAAGCCUUACAAAUGUCAUGAAUGCGGCAAGGUCUUUAGGCGUAAUUCACACCUUGCAAGGCAUCAGCUAAUUCAUACUGGAGAGAAACCUUAUAAGUGUAAUGAGUGUGGCAAAGCCUUUAGAGCACAUUCAAACCUAACUACCCAUCAGGUCAUCCAUACUGGAGAAAAGCCUUACAAAUGUAAUGAAUGUGGCAAGGUCUUCACUCAAAAUUCACACCUUGCAAAUCAUCAAAGAAUUCAUACUGGAGUGAAGCCUUAUAUGUGUAAUGAGUGCGGCAAAGCCUUCAGUGUGUAUUCAAGCCUAACUACCCAUCAGGUCAUCCAUACUGGAGAAAAACCUUACAAAUGUAAUGAGUGUGGCAAGGUCUUCACUCAGAAUUCACACCUUGCAAGACAUCGGGGAAUUCAUACUGGAGAGAAACCUUAUAAAUGUAAUGAAUGUGGCAAGGUCUUUAGGCAUAAUUCAUACCUUUCAAGGCAUCAGCGAAUUCAUACUGGAGAGAAACCUUACAAGUAUAAUGAGUAUGGCAAAGCCUUUAGUGAACAUUCAAACCUAACUACCCAUCAGGUCAUCCAUACUGGUGAAAAACCUUACAAAUGUAAUGAGUGUGGCAAGGUCUUCACUCAGAAUUCACACCUUGCAAGACAUCGGAGAGUUCAUACUGGAGGUAAACCUUACCAGUGUAAUGAAUGUGGCAAAGCCUUUAGUCAAACAUCAAAGCUUGCAAGGCAUCAGAGAGUUCAUACUGGAGAGAAACCAUAUGAGUGUAAUCAGUGUGGGAAAGCCUUUAGUGUCCGUUCAAGCCUAACUACCCAUCAGGCAAUCCAUACUGGAAAAAAACCUUACAAAUGCAAUGAGUGUGGGAAGGUCUUCACUCAGAAUUCACACCUUGCAAGACAUCGGGGAAUUCAUACUGGAGAGAAACCUUACAAGUGUAAUGAGUGUGGCAAAGCCUUUAGUCAAACUUCAAAACUUGCAAGGCAUCAGAGAAUUCAUACCGGAGAGAAACCAUAUGAGUGUGGGAAACCCUUUAGUAUCUGUUCAAGCCUAACUACCCAUCAGACAAUCCAUACUGGUGGGAAACCUUACAAAUGUAACGUGUGGAAAGUUCUAAAGUCAGAGUUCAAACCUUGCAAGCCAUCACAGAAUUCAUAGUGGAGAGAAACCUUACAAAUGAAGGUGGUAACUUUUGCAGUUAGAAUUCAUUCCUUUGACAACGUCAGAGAAUUUAUGCCUGAGAGAUUCCUUGAAAAUGCAAUGACUGGCUGGGUGCAGUGGCUCAUGCCUGUAAUCCCAACACUUUGGGAGUCCGAGGCAGGUGGAUCACCUGAGGUCAGGAGUUCAAGACCAGCCUGACCAACAUGGCGAAACCCCAUUUCUACUAAAAGUACACAAUUAGCUAGGCCUGGUGGCGUGCGCCUGUAAUCCCAGCUAUAUAGGAGGCUGAGGCAGGAGAAUCACUUGAACCCAGGAGGCGGAGGUUGCAGUGAGCCAAGAUCGUGCCAAUGCACUCCAUCCUGGGCAAAAAGAGCAAAACUCCAUCUUAAAGGAAAAAAAAAAAAUGCAAUGACUGUGGCAAACUCCUCAUGAGUUCAAGUAUUAAUAGACAUCCAAGAGUCCAUAAUAAUGAGAAAUCACAUAAAUGUACUGUGUGUGACAGAGGCUUUAUUCAGGCCUCACAGCUUUGCAGGCAUUAAAAUCUACGUAUUUGAUGGAACCACACAAAUGUAAUGUGUAAGAGCAUCCUGAAGCUCUUACUCUAAGACUGUAACUGUAGGUGAGGAUUCAUACAAAGAGUGACUCAGUCUCUAGUUCUUUGAUUCACUUUUAAAAUGAUAAACUGCACAAUAAUUACACGUUCCAAUAUGGUAAAACUUAAGACAUUAUAUAUUUCAAAGGUCAAAGGACAUUUGGAAAUGGCUACUUACCUUCAGGUUAUAAAAUCUUUUAUUCCAUUGUUUGAGGUUUCUCAAAAAGGCUACUGUUUGUGACUUUCAACCUGAACUAUGGAUCUGUGGCUAUUUUGCAUCCUUAAGCACCUUUCGUGGUGCCUAUCUGGGAAAGAACCACAGUAUGGAAAGGCUUACUUCAUUACAUGAGGAUCAUUUUUAUCCAUGUUUAUUGAAGAAGGAGGACUCUGCCUUGUAAAAUUAAAUAUUCUCUCAAUUGAGAGACCAUGGUUUUGGGGCAGAAAAUAAUGUAAAACUAUGAUAUCAAUCAUCAUACUGAUUGUGUUCAGGGUGCUUUUCUGAGAGAAAGACACCAUGGGUUUUAGGGAAGUAAGGCUCUACCUGCAUUGAGCAGGCCAAGACCUCAGGACACUGGAAUUUUUAUGAGAGGAGAGUAAUAAGUUAUUAGUGACUGAUUAUGUGAUGGGAAUAGUGCAGGGGAAAUGGUUGCCACUUUCUCUACUGAAUGGCAAUAGCUGUUUUAUAGCAGAGAUUGAUGAAAAAUAGGCUUAUUUUUGAAAUUGAAGAGGUAACAGUUAUUAGAGUGGAGAGCUUGGUCAGAAAAACCAGAAUACCAUGGUUUUUUUUGUUUUGUUUUGUUUUUAGUAGAAUUCACACUAAUUGCUGGAAUUACAUUUUGCUACAGUUUUAUUAAGAAUGUGUCACAGACAUAAUGUUUUGCUAAAAAAAAUUCAACGUUUUCUUAUAACUAUAAACAAAUCACAUUCUUUGUACCAACAUCAUUUUAUCCUACCUCAGUAGGAUACUUCAUAGCAGAUAAUAACAAUACACUCAGUCUUUUAGGUUGGAGGAUGUAGAACAAUUUUUUUUUUCUUUGUGGAAUCAACAUACAAUUUUGGGAAAAUGUAAUCAUACUCUGCACUUGAAUUAUUCUCUCUACACUCUGCCUUAGAAUAUUUAUAUGGAUAUAAUGAAAAUCCCAUAGAAAGUGCAGUUUUCAUACUCUUACACUCUGAAAGCUGCCACAGUGUUGGUGAAUAUAUACCAUAUUAUAUUUUUACAUGCUUGUGUGCUAAAUAACUAUGGCAUGCAUCUUUAUUUACAUGAAGUGAAAAUACAAAUAUAGAAAGUGUAUGGGCUGGGUGUGGUGGUUCAUGCCUGUAAUCCUAGCACUUUGAGAGCCCAAGGCAGGGGGGUCACUUGAGUCCAGGAGUUUGAACCAGCCAGGACAACAUGGCAAAACCCUGUCUCUACAAAAAAAAUAGAAAUAUUACCCAGGCAGGGUGGCUCAUGCCUGUAGUCCCAGCUCCUCAGGGAGACUGAGGCAGGUGGAUCACUUGAGCCUGGAGGCAGAGGUUGCAGUGAGCCAAGAUCGCGCCAUUGCACUCCAGCCUGGGUGACAGAGCGAGACCCUGUCUCAAAAAAAACAAUUGUAUGAAAAAUAUUGGCUGGGUGUGGUGGCUCACACCUGUAAUCCCAGCACUUAGGGAGGCCAAGGCGGGUGGAUCAUGGGGUCAGAAAAUCGAGACCACCCUGGCCAACACAGUGAAACCCCAUCUCUACUAAAAAAUACCAAAUAUAUAUAUAUUGGUUGGAUGUGGUGGCAUGCGCCUGUAAUCCCAGCUACUCGGGAGGCUGAGGCAGGAGAAUCACUUGAACCCAGGAGGUGGAGGUUGCAGUGAGCCGAGAUUGCCACUGCACUCCAGCCUGGGCGAGAAAGUGAGACUCCGUCUCAAAAAAAAAAAUUAUGAAAUUAUAAAUAGUGCAGAAUAACAAAAAUAACACUAAGAAUGCUAUGCUCACAUAAUUUGACAAGACUAAUAUUCAUGAGUUUCCUCUUAAAAAUGAACAUAUAUAAUGGAAAUUUUGUUUUUGUAGGUAAACUAGAAGUUUCAUAAAUUUAGCCUUAUCAUGUUUUUGGUAAUGUUAAUUUGUCACCUCUCCACAGGAAGUGUAUUGAACUCCAUUUACAGUUUGGUUUAGAUAUGGAAAAUGAGGAUGCUGAACAAUGAAGUUUUAGGGAAAUGUGUAUUGCAUAAUGAGGCUUUCUGUGAGAAGCAGGAUUGACUUCCCAAACUGGUCCAAAAUGGCUUGAGAGAGCAGGGAUAAAUAACUUGCUUGGGGUGUUAUGGUAAUAACCUUUAAUAAAAGGGUGGGUUGGGGUGAGGAUCCCACACGUGAUUUGAACUUCCAUCUAGUGCCAAAGGAGGGAACACGGACAUUAUCAGCUUGGCCAGAUGGGCAGAAUAAGAAGAGGGAGUGCAGAGGUAUAAAUGGUGGUAUAAGACAAAAAUCACAAAAUGGAAACUGACUGUAGUACAACACUGAAUAUUUACUCUUGCAACUUCUGAUUUCUGGCCAGGCAUGGCCAGAAAUUACAGGCUCAUGCCUGUAAUCCCAGCACUUUGGGAGCCCGAGGCAGGUGGAUCACCUUAGGUCAGGAGCUCAAGACGAGCCUGGCCAACAUGGUGAAACCCCAUCUCUACUAAAAAUACAAAAAUUAGCCAGGUGUGGUGGCGCACUCCUGUAGUCCUAGCUACCAGGGAGGCUGAGGCAGGAGAAUCACUUGAACCCGGGAGACGGAGGUUGCAGUGAGCUGAGAUCUCACCACUGCACUCCAGCCUGGGCAAUAGAGUGAGACUCUCAAAAAAACAAAAGAAAUUUCUAACUUCUUUGUUAGGGAAGACCUCCGCUUUCUUCAUAAUAGUAGAUAAUACUCUUCCUUUCUGCUGAACCCAUAGGGCCCAUUACACAACGUCAUUCUUGAAAAUAUUUGUGAAAUGCUGUUUAAAUUGCCUAAAAUAUUUUUACAGUAGUUCAAUGCAAAUGAAUUUGUGGAAAAGUUUAUUACAUAAUAUGAUCAAGCAAUUUUAGCCAAAGGGCAUUUUUCCAAAGGCUGUGUUAUAUUCAUGUCUUGUUCAGUUUAUGGUAUUGUGUAACAUAUUCUCCAUAGCUUCUUUUCUUUUUUUUUUUCUUUUUCUUUUUAGACGUGGGGUCUCGCUAUGUUGGCCAGGUUGGUCUUGAACUCUUGGCCUCAAGCAUUCCUCCUGCCUCAGCUUCCCAAAGUGCUAGGAUUACAGCCAUGAGCCAAUAGUAGUAAAAUGACUUUUUGUUUUUGUAUAUGAUUUUUACUUUAAGGAUUUUUUCCUUCCAUACAUUUUAAUCCAAAUUAUAUGUUUACUGCAUUUCUUCUCUGUGUUACUCCAGUGAACACUUAGAAAAUACAUAAAUGAGGGUGUUGUUUAGAAAUAAAAUUUUGUGACAUGAAAAUGUAUGUAAAACAAUGGCAGGUACAGACUAGGUUCUCUGUAAAUAGGAAAAUGGAGUGUCCUUGUAAAUCUUUAGUUCAAUUAAAGUACAGGGAUACUAGAUGGUGAAAUGAAGUCUCUUAAUAUGGAAGUUAUCAAAGAUCAGAUGCUUGAAAAUCAAGCGUGUGGAGGUUAACCAGCAUCUGGAGAAGUAAAUGAAAAUACAGUUAAUAAGAGAGUCCCCAAGAUAUUAAUUAUCAUUUAUGCAAAGGAGAUAAUUUCUCUCAUUGAAUCCCUGGAGGCAAUUCAACUUCCUACUGUGGCUGGUAUUUCUUUUCUGAGCCAGAGGAUCUUACAGCAAAACAUGAUAUUUGUGCAACUUUUGCAAUGACAGCUGCCAUUUAAUAUACUCCCCUUAGAUUUGUUUCCAUUUUAAAAAACUGAUAUAUAUUCUUUAAUAAGUGAUUUAUCUUUGCAUAUAUAUUUUAUAUCAAUCACAUUUAGAGUAAGAAUCACAGUUAUUAAUGCUUUAUGUGUAACAACUGAAUCAUCAGCUCCUGAAAUAAGUAUUAAUGAUAUUCUCAUUUCAGAGGUGAGGAAACUUAGGACAGAUAAGCAAAAUAAUCAAAUUAGGCUGGGCACAGUGGCUCAUGCCUGUAAUCCCAGCACUUUGGGAGGCCGAGGCGGGGGGAUCACCUGAGGUCAGGAAUUCGAGACCAGCCUGAUCAACAUGGUGAAACCCCGUCUCUACUAAAAAUACAAAAAUUAGCUGGGUGUGAUGGCGGGCGCCUGUAAUCCCAGCUAUUCGGGAGGCUGAGGCAGGAGAAUUGCUUGAGCCUGGGAGGCGGAUGUUGCAGUUAGCCGAGUUCCCACCAUUGCACUCCAGUCUCAGUGACAGAGCGGGACUCCAUCUCUCUCUCUCUCUCUCUCUCUCUUUCUCUCUCUCUCUCUCUCUCUCUCUCUCUAUAUAUAUAUAUAUAUAUAUAUAUAUAUAUAUAUAUAUAUUUAGAAAAUGGGUAGAACUAUGAAGAGACAUUUCACUGAAGCAGUUAUACUGAGAUAAAUAGGCACAUAAAAAGAUUUCCAACAUCACCAUCCAUCAAAUCUCAGAUCUCAGCAUAUUCUGCUUUAAAAGACUCAUCUUGUCACAUUUCAGUAAGAGGCAGAAUCGAGAUUUGAAUCCAUGUUGUCUGGUUGCAAAGACAAAGCUUUUAAUGAUGAUGCUACAGUAACAAUGCUAGUUAUUUUUGUCCUUUACUCACCAUCUAUACCUAUUUUGUUAGUAUCUCUUGUAAUUUUUAAAUGGUUUAUCUUCAUAUAUCAUUGUGAUUGUGGUAACUUUGUAUUAAAUCUAUAUUUUUAUAGAUCAA